AGGACAUCCUCUCCAAUCCACCACACACCACCUUACCCCUCUGCUGGCAAGAGGGGACCUGAUUCAUCCUCACGCUAAACACUCAUUCUACCCAACUGAUUGAGACAGAACAGAAGAUAAACUGAAACUUCUCUGCCUUCCCGCUGCAAGAGUGAAUGAGCGAUCCCUCUCAACUGACUCAAAAUGUUUGCCUCACCCAGGAGAUGGAGCUCUCGAAGGCCUUCUCUGGCCAGCGGACACUCCUAUCUGCCAUCCUCAGCAUGCUAUCACUCAGCUUCUCCACAACAUCCCUGCUCAGCAACUACUGGUUUGUGGGCACACAGAAGGUGCCCAAGCCCCUGUGCGAGAAAGGUCUGGCAGCCAAGUGCUUUGACAUGCCAGUGUCCCUGGAUGGAGAUACCAACACAUCCACCCAGGAGGUGGUACAAUACAACUGGGAGACUGGGGAUGACCGGUUCUCCUUCCGGAGCUUCCGGAGUGGCAUGUGGCUAUCCUGUGAGGAAACUGUGGAAGAACCAGCUAAAAGCGAGAUGGAAGAGGAAUUAAAAAAAUGUGUGUAUUUACAUUUAUAUUUAUUAUUGUGCCACUUAGCACUGCUCCAUCCCCAGUCCUGGAAACAAUUUAGAGCCCUUCGGUCCAGUGGUACAGCGGCAGCAAAAGGGGAGAGGUGCCGAAGUUUCAUUGAACUUACACCACCAGCCAAGAGAGGUGAGAAAGGACUACUGGAAUUUGCCACGUUGCAAGGCCCAUGUCACCCCACUCUCCGAUUUGGAGGGAAGCGGUUGAUGGAGAAGGCUUCCCUCCCCUCCCCUCCCUUGGGGCUUUGUGGCAAAAAUCCUAUGGUUAUCCCUGGGAACGCAGAUCACCUACAUCGGACUUCAAUUCAUCAGCUUCCUCCUGCUACUAACAGACUUGCUACUCACUGGGAACCCUGCCUGUGGGCUCAAACUGAGCGCCUUUGCUGCUGUUUCCUCUGUCCUGUCAGGGCUCUGCCUUCCUGUUUCCUUGGUAGGUCUCCUGGGGAUGGUGGCCCACAUGAUGUAUUCACAAGUCUUCCAAGCGACUGUCAACUUGGGUCCAGAAGACUGGAGACCACAUGUUUGGAAUUAUGGCUGGGCCUUCUACAUGGCCUGGCUCUCCUUCACCUGCUGCAUGGCGUCGGCUGUCACCACCUUCAACACGUACACCAGGAUGGUGCUGGAGUUCAAGUGCAAGCAUAGUAAGAGCUUCAAGGAAAACCCGAACUGCCUACCACAUCACCAUCAGUGUUUCCCUCGGCGGCUGUCAAGUGCAGCCCCCACCGUGGGUCCUUUGACCAGCUACCACCAGUAUCAUAAUCAGCCCAUCCACUCUGUCUCUGAGGGAGUCGACUUCUACUCCGAGCUGCGGAACAAGGGAUUUCAAAGAGGGGCCAGCCAGGAGCUGAAAGAAGCAGUUAGGUCAUCUGUAGAGGAAGAGCAGUGUUAGGAGUUAAGCGGGUUUGGGGAGUAGGCUUGAGCCCUACCUUACACGUCUGCUGAUUAUCAACAUGUGCUUAAGCCAACAUCCGUCUCUUGAGCAUGGUUUUUAGAGGCUACGAAUAAGGCUAUGAAUAAGGGUUAUCUUUAAGUCCUAAGGGAUUCCUGGGUGCCACUGCUCUCUUUUCCUCUACAGCUCCAUCUUGUUUCACCCACCCCACAUCUCACACAUCCAGAAUUCCCUUCUUUACUGAUAGUUUCUGUGCCAGGUUCUGGGCUAAACCAUGGAGAUAAAAAGAAGAGUAAAAUACACUUCCCGACCUUAAGGAUCUGAUACAUCUAGUUAUUGGUCUGGAAAUUGGAGAAAUGGAGGUGAGCAAAUUAACGGUAGUGUGACUGUGGCUCAACUUUCCAUGGUACGCGCGAAUUGUUCUGGAAGUCACAGAUGGGAAGACAGAAGCGCCCCUGAGUGCUUUGUCAUAUAGCACAGAAGUCCUCCACACUGCCUGGGACAGUGUCCUGCAUCCACACAGUAGGUACCCAGUAAAAGUGUUAUUAAAUAUUGUCCCAGGAGCCCUUAGGAGAGUGGUUUAACAUGAGAAGGCGCCAACAGCACACAGGGUCAGGGUCACUUCUAGAAAUAGCCCACCAAGGCUAUUCAGAUUGGACUGUGGUUCCCUUCUGGACAGUCACACCAGGGACUUCCCAGUGAACAAGGGGGCAUAGGCUCCUCUCUGGAUCCCACCUUUUCAUCCCUUCUGAGAAAUGUACCCUAUUAUUUCCUUCAUAAAGAAUGCCACCCAUCUGAUUCCUCAAGAAUCUAGACCUAGAAAUACCAUUUGACCCAGCCAUCCCAUUACUGGGUAGAUACCCAAAGGAUUACAAAUCAUGCUGCUAUAAAGACACAUGCACACAUAUGUUUAUUACGGCACUAUUUAUAAUAGCAAAGACUUGGAACCAACCCAAAUGUCCAUCAGUGAUAGACUGGAUUAAGAAAAUGUGGCACAUAUACACCAUGGAAUACUAUGCAGCCAUAAAGAAGGAUGAGUUUAUGCCCUUUGUAGGGACAUGGAUGAAGCUGGAAACCAUCAUUCUGAGCAAACUAUCGCAAGGAUAGAAAACCAAACACUGCAUAUUCUCACUCACAGGUGGGAAUUGAACAAUAAAAACACUUGGACACAGGGUGGGGAACAUCACACACCGGGCCUGUCAUGGGGUGGGGGGAGGGGGGAGGGAUAGCAUUAGGAGAUAUACUAACGUAAAUGACGAGUUAAUGGGUGCAGCACACCAACAUGGCACAUGUAUACAUAUGUAACAAAUCUGCACGUUGUGCACAUGUACCCUAGAACUUAAAAAAAAAAAAAAAAGAAUGCCACCCA